AUUCGGGGAGACUGCAGGCCAACCGGGAGGCUGAGUUCGAAGCUAGCAGGGCGGCGAAGCCAGUGUCGCCCGCGGCGUUGAGAAGACGGUGUGGCCCCGGAGAGGGUGGAGACAACUGUGACGGGCUUCCCGGCUGCCCGAAGUGGGAGUGGUGUGGGGCUGCAGGAAGGAGAGAGGAAGAGGAGCAGAAGGGGGCAGCAGCGGACGCCGCUAACGGCCUCCCUCGGCGCUGACAGGCUGGGCCGGCGCCCGGCUCGCUUGGGUGUUCGCGUCGCCACUUCGGCUUCUCGGCCGGUCGGGCCCCUCGGCCCGGGCUUGCGGCGCGCGUCGGGGCUGAGGGCUGCUGCGGCGCAGGGAGAGGCCUGGUCCUCGCUGCCGAGGGAUGUGAGUGGGAGCUGAGCCCACACUGGAGGGCCCCCGAGGGCCCAGCCUGGAGGUCGUUCAGAGCCGUGCCCGUCCCGGGGCUUCGCAGACCUUGACCCGCCGGGUUUCAGAAGCAGGCAACAGGAACAAGAUGUGAACUGUUUCUCUUCUGCAGAAAAAGAGGCUCUUCCUCCUCCUCCCGCGACGGCAAAUGUUCUGAAAAAGACUCUGCAUGGGAAUGGCCUGCCUUACGAUGACAGAAAUGGAGGGAACAUCCACCUCUUCUAUAUAUCAGAAUGGUGAUAUUUCUGGAAAUGCCAAUUCUAUGAAGCAAAUAGAUCCAGUUCUUCAGGUGUAUCUUUACCAUUCCCUUGGGAAAUCUGAGGCAGAUUAUCUGACCUUUCCAUCUGGGGAGUAUGUUGCAGAAGAAAUCUGUAUUGCUGCUUCUAAAGCUUGUGGUAUCACACCUGUGUAUCAUAAUAUGUUUGCUUUAAUGAGUGAAACAGAAAGGAUCUGGUAUCCACCCAACCAUGUCUUCCAUAUAGAUGAGUCAACCAGGCAUAAUGUACUCUACAGAAUAAGAUUUUACUUUCCUCGUUGGUAUUGCAGUGGCAGCAACAGAGCCUAUCGGCAUGGAAUAUCUCGAGGUGCUGAAGCUCCUCUUCUUGAUGACUUUGUCAUGUCUUACCUCUUUGCUCAGUGGCGGCAUGAUUUUGUGCACGGAUGGAUAAAAGUACCUGUGACUCAUGAAACACAGGAAGAAUGUCUUGGGAUGGCAGUGUUAGAUAUGAUGAGAAUAGCCAAAGAAAACGAUCAAACCCCACUGGCCAUCUAUAACUCUAUCAGCUACAAGACAUUCUUACCAAAAUGUAUUCGAGCAAAGAUCCAAGACUAUCAUAUUUUGACAAGGAAGCGAAUAAGGUACAGAUUUCGCAGAUUUAUUCAGCAAUUCAGCCAAUGCAAAGCCACUGCCAGAAACUUGAAACUUAAGUAUCUUAUAAAUCUGGAAACUCUGCAGUCUGCCUUCUACACAGAGAAAUUUGAAGUAAAAGAACCUGGAAGUGGUCCUUCAGGUGAGGAGAUUUUUGCAACCAUUAUAAUAACUGGAAACGGUGGAAUUCAGUGGUCAAGAGGGAAACAUAAAGAAAGUGAGACACUGACAGAACAGGAUUUACAGUUAUAUUGCGAUUUUCCUAAUAUUAUUGAUGUCAGUAUUAAGCAAGCAAACCAAGAGGGUUCAAAUGAAAGCCGAGUUGUAACUAUCCAUAAGCAAGAUGGUAAAAAUCUGGAAAUUGAACUUAGCUCAUUAAGGGAAGCUUUGUCUUUCGUGUCAUUAAUUGAUGGAUAUUAUAGAUUAACUGCAGAUGCACAUCAUUACCUCUGUAAAGAAGUAGCACCUCCAGCCGUGCUUGAAAAUAUACAAAGCAACUGUCAUGGCCCAAUUUCGAUGGAUUUUGCCAUUAGUAAACUGAAGAAAGCAGGUAAUCAGACUGGACUGUAUGUACUUCGAUGCAGUCCUAAGGACUUUAAUAAAUAUUUUUUGACUUUUGCUGUCGAGCGAGAAAAUGUCAUUGAAUAUAAACACUGUUUGAUUACAAAAAAUGAGAAUGAAGAGUACAACCUCAGUGGGACAAAGAAGAACUUCAGCAGUCUUAAAGAUCUUUUGAAUUGUUACCAGAUGGAAACUGUUCGCUCAGACAAUAUAAUUUUCCAGUUUACUAAAUGCUGUCCCCCAAAGCCAAAAGAUAAAUCAAACCUUCUAGUCUUCAGAACGAAUGGUGUUUCUGAUGUACCAACCUCACCAACAUUACAGAGGCCUACUCAUAUGAACCAAAUGGUGUUUCACAAAAUCAGAAAUGAAGAUUUGAUAUUUAAUGAAAGCCUUGGCCAAGGCACUUUUACAAAGAUUUUUAAAGGCGUACGAAGAGAAGUAGGAGACUACGGUCAACUGCAUGAAACAGAAGUUCUUUUAAAAGUUCUGGAUAAAGCACACAGAAACUAUUCAGAGUCUUUCUUUGAAGCAGCAAGUAUGAUGAGCAAGCUUUCUCACAAGCAUUUGGUUUUAAAUUAUGGAGUAUGUGUCUGUGGAGACGAGAAUAUUCUGGUUCAGGAGUUUGUAAAAUUUGGAUCACUAGAUACAUAUCUGAAAAAGAAUAAAAAUUGUAUAAAUAUAUUAUGGAAACUUGAAGUUGCUAAACAGUUGGCAUGGGCCAUGCAUUUUCUAGAAGAAAACACCCUUAUUCAUGGGAAUGUAUGUGCCAAAAAUAUUCUGCUUAUCAGAGAAGAAGACAGGAAGACAGGAAAUCCUCCUUUCAUCAAACUUAGUGAUCCUGGCAUUAGUAUUACAGUUUUGCCAAAGGACAUUCUUCAGGAGAGAAUACCAUGGGUACCACCUGAAUGCAUUGAAAAUCCUAAAAAUUUAAAUUUGGCAACAGACAAAUGGAGUUUUGGUACCACUUUGUGGGAAAUCUGCAGUGGAGGAGAUAAACCUCUAAGUGCUCUGGAUUCUCAAAGAAAGCUACAAUUUUAUGAAGAUAGGCAUCAGCUUCCUGCACCAAAGUGGGCAGAAUUAGCAAACCUUAUAAAUAAUUGUAUGGAUUAUGAACCAGAUUUCAGGCCUUCUUUCAGAGCCAUCAUACGAGAUCUUAACAGUUUGUUUACUCCAGAUUAUGAACUAUUAACAGAAAAUGACAUGUUACCAAAUAUGAGGAUAGGUGCCCUGGGGUUUUCUGGUGCCUUUGAAGACCGGGAUCCUACACAGUUUGAAGAGAGACAUUUGAAAUUUCUACAGCAACUUGGCAAGGGUAAUUUUGGGAGUGUGGAGAUGUGCCGGUAUGACCCUCUACAGGACAACACUGGGGAGGUGGUCGCUGUAAAAAAGCUUCAGCAUAGUACUGAAGAGCACCUAAGAGACUUUGAAAGGGAAAUUGAAAUCCUGAAAUCCCUACAGCAUGACAACAUUGUAAAGUACAAGGGAGUGUGCUACAGUGCUGGUCGGCGUAAUCUAAAAUUAAUUAUGGAAUAUUUACCAUAUGGAAGUUUACGAGACUAUCUUCAAAAACAUAAAGAACGGAUAGAUCACAUAAAACUUCUGCAGUACACAUCUCAGAUAUGCAAGGGUAUGGAGUAUCUUGGUACAAAAAGGUAUAUCCACAGGGAUCUGGCAACGAGAAAUAUAUUGGUGGAGAACGAGAACAGAGUUAAAAUUGGAGAUUUUGGGUUAACCAAAGUCUUGCCACAAGACAAAGAAUACUAUAAAGUAAAAGAACCUGGUGAAAGUCCCAUAUUCUGGUAUGCUCCAGAAUCACUGACAGAGAGCAAGUUUUCUGUGGCCUCAGAUGUUUGGAGCUUUGGAGUGGUUCUGUAUGAACUUUUCACAUACAUUGAGAAGAGUAAAAGUCCACCAGCGGAAUUUAUGCGUAUGAUUGGCAAUGACAAACAAGGACAGAUGAUCGUGUUCCAUUUGAUAGAACUUUUGAAGAAUAAUGGAAGAUUACCAAGACCAGAUGGAUGCCCAGAUGAGAUCUAUAUGAUCAUGACAGAAUGCUGGAACAAUAAUGUAAAUCAACGCCCCUCCUUUAGGGAUCUAGCUCUUCGAGUGGAUCAAAUAAGGGAUAACAUGGCUGGAUGAAAGAAAUGACCUUCAUUCUGAGACCAAAGUAGAUUUACAGAACAAAGUUUUAUAUUUCACAUUGCUGUGGACUAUUAUUACAUAUAUCAUUAUUAUAUAAAUCAUGAUGCUAGCCAGCAAAGAUGUGAAAAUAUCUGCUCAAAACUUUCAAAGUUUAGUAAGUUUUUCUUCAUGAGGCCACCAGUAAAAGACAUUAAUGAGAAUUCCUUAGCAAGGAUUUUGUAAGAAGUUUCUUAAACAUUGUCAGUUAACAUCACUCUUGUCUGGCAAAAGAAAAAAAAUAGACUUUUUCAACUCAGCUUUUUGAGACCUGAAAAAAUUAUUAUGUAAAUUUUGCAAUGUUAAAGAUGCACAGAAUAUGUAUGUAUAGUUUUUACCACAGUGGAUGUAUAAUACCUUGGCAUCUUGUGUGAUGUUUUACACACAUGAGGGCUGGUGUUCAUUAAUACUGUUUUCUAAUUUUUCCAUAGUUAAUCUAUAAUUAAUUACUUCACUAUACAAACAAAUUAAGAUGUUCAGAUAAUUGAAUAAGUACCUUUGUGUCCUUGUUCAUUUAUAUCGCUGGCCAGCAUUAUAAGCAGGUGUAUACUUUUAGCUUGUAGUUCCAUGUACUGUAAAUAUUUUUCACAUAAAGGGAACAAAUGUCUAGUUUUAUUUGUAUAGGAAAUUUCCCUGACCCUAAAUAAUACAUUUUGAAAUGAAACAAGCUUACAAAGAUAUAAUCUAUUUUAUUAUGGUUUCCCUUGUAUCUAUUUGUGGUGAAUGUGUUUUUUAAAUGGAACUAUCUCCAAAUUUUUCUAAGACUACUAUGAACAGUUUUCUUUUAAAAUUUUGAGAUUAAGAAUGCCAGGAAUAUUGUCAUCCUUUGAGCUGCUGACUGCCAAUAACAUUCUUCGAUCUCUGGGAUUUAUGCUCAUGAACUAAAUUUAAGCUUAAGCCAUAAAAUAGAUUAGAUUGUUUUUUAAAAAUGGAUAGCUCAUUAAGAAGUGCAGCAGGUUAAGAAUUUUUUCCUAAAGACUGUAUAUUUGAGGGGUUUCAGAAUUUUGCAUUGCAGUCAUAGAAGAGAUUUAUUUCCUUUUUAGAGGGGAAAUGAGGUAAAUAAGUAAAAAAGUAUGCUUGUUAAUUUUAUUCAAGAAUGCCAGUAGAAAAUUCAUAACGUGUAUCUUUAAGAAAAAUGAGCAUACAUCUUAAAUCUUUUCAAUUAAGUAUAAGGGGUUGUUCGUUGUUGUCAUUUGUUAUAGUGCUACUCCACUUUAGACACCAUAGCUAAAAUAAAAUAUGGUGGGUUUUGUGUGUGUGUGUGUGUGUGUGUGUGUGUGUGUGUGUGUGUUAUUUAUACAAAACUUAAAAUACUUGCUGUUUUGAUUAAAAAGAAAAUAGUUUCUUACUUUAUUUUUACUGGUAUGUUCUACUUUUUUGAAAGUUGUACUGAAGACUUCUGAUUUUGGGUUGAAGGGAAGGAAAAGGAAGAAAUGUUUUUUACAUUCAUUAUUAUACUUAAAGCAUUUUUAAAGCAUUUUAAUAGUUCUGGAUGCAGAAAUCAUCUAAAAUGACAGUGAAUUAGGUUUUAAAAAGAUUUUAGAUUUUUUUGAAAGUUUAAUUUUUAUUUGUAAAGACUCCUCAAGGAUUUGUAUAUGCAACACAGUAAGGAGAUCUUCCAUUUUACUACCUUUCAAGUGAAAAAUAGCCUAUCAUACAAUAUGCUUGAUUUCAGAUUUUCAUACUAAAACUUAACUACAUACUUAAAAGUAGGUUCUUAUCAAGGGUCUCUAACAUUGCUUUUUAAAACAAGAUGUGAACUAACUUUUCUUAAACAUUUUUUUAAAUGCUUCAUCUUUUAGUUUUAUAUAAAGAAUCCCACAUGUACAUUCUUGUUUUUAGAAUGGGGUGACUACCUUAUUAUAAAAUUCCAAGUUUCCAAGAGACUUCUUUUCAUUGAGGCUUCGUAAAGUUUUCCAUUUUGAUUCUGACUACACAUAAAAAUAAGAUAACCCUGUAGUUAUUAAGUUGGUUCUGUACAAGAAACAGGUAAGUAAUUAUUGUACCAGUUAAUGCCAAAAUAUUUUUCACGUUAAUAUUCUUCAGAAACAAGGGUAAAGGUAUUCUUAGAAUUAUGUAAUUCUGUAACUAUUCCAGUAUAUUAAGUUAUACAAUCUUUAUAUAAAUGACUUUUUCCAUGGGUACUUGUUUGGAAAAUAGUCACUUUUUCACGCUAUUUAUAUAUGCUGCCAGUAACACUAUAAUUUGCUAUGGAAGAGUGUUCUUUUAACCUAAGGCUUCUAGUUUACAGUCAAGUGUAAUUUUCAUCACAACUAUAACUUCUGGUAUUUAAAUUUUAUUUAAACAGCUACAAAAGAGUUAGCAAAUACCUACAGUUCUGUAUCUAUAGAGCCAAUCUUGAUGGUGGGUGUGGCAUUAUGUGCUCACUUUAUUGAGCCUAUGUUAAUUUCUUUAGCAUGCUCCCCCUAAAUUGAAAUAGUGAUGUAGUAAAUAUUCAGAAGCGAUUUUCUUUUGCAUUUUUACCUAACCAAGGAAACGGGCCACACACCUUGGUUUAGGGAUGUUGUGAUAGCUUACCUUCCAGUUUUUAAGAAAUGCUUCCUACAACUGCUGUCAACCACUGUAUUGUCUUUAAUGAACACUGUUGUAUCCCAUCCUAAUUCUUGUACUGAAAUUAUUUCUCAUGAAAGUUUCUCUAAUAUUUCUAAUGAAAGUUUCUCUAAUUUGGGGGCAUAAUGUACUAAGAAUCAGUUUGCUGUAUAUUAGAAUAAAUAGUAACAGUAAGUCAGCAGGAUUAUCCAAACAAAAGACUAGGUUUUAUGAGAUAAGCUUGAUUUAAGAAAAAAACAAUUAAAGUAUGAAUAUCAGAAAUACUGUGUGUUUACUCUCAGAUUUUAGUUGGUUGGAUUUAAUAUCAAGAUAACUAGCUGCUAAGCGUUUCAUAAUUCUCACAGUGAUAUUAGAUUUCAAAAUGACACUGAGAGAACUGAAAAACUACAUCAGUCAAAUUCAUGUAUGUAUAUCAUAUAGCCUUUAACUUUUUACAUUAAUCAGAUUCUUAGUAAAAUGCAGACUGUAUACCUAAAUAUUAAAAUAUUUACUUUUAUAAUCUUACCUUUUAUUUCAAUAUAAAUAAAAUUCUUCUUAGGUUAAAAAA